GUAAGUCAACAAUGUCCUGGGAUUGGGACACACUUUCUGGGCACUGCUGGCCAGUCCCAAAAUGGAACAUAAGGAAGUGGUUCUUCUACUUCUUUUAUUUCUGAAAUCAGCAGCACCUGAGCAAAGCCAUGUGGUCCAGGAUUGCUACCAUGGUGAUGGACAGAGUUAUCGAGGCACGUACUCCACCACUGUCACAGGAAGGACCUGCCAAGCUUGGUCAUCUAUGACACCACAUCAACAUAAUAGGACCACAGAAAACUACCCAAAUGCUGGCUUGAUCAUGAACUACUGCAGGAAUCCAGAUGCUGUGGCAGCUCCUUAUUGUUAUACGAGGGAUCCCGGUGUCAGGUGGGAGUACUGCAACCUGACGCAAUGCUCAGACGCAGAAGGGACUGCCGUCGCGCCUCCGACUGUUACCCCGGUUCCAAGCCUAGAGGCUCCUUCCGAACAAGCACCGACUGAGCAAAGGCCUGGGGUGCAGGAGUGCUACCAUGGUAAUGGACAGAGUUAUCGAGGCACAUACUCCACCACUGUCACAGGAAGAACCUGCCAAGCUUGGUCAUCUAUGACACCACACUCGCAUAGUCGGACCCCAGAAUACUACCCAAAUGCUGGCUUGAUCAUGAACUACUGCAGGAAUCCAGAUGCUGUGGCAGCUCCUUAUUGUUAUACGAGGGAUCCCGGUGUCAGGUGGGAGUACUGCAACCUGACGCAAUGCUCAGACGCAGAAGGGACUGCCGUCGCGCCUCCGACUGUUACCCCGGUUCCAAGCCUAGAGGCUCCUUCCGAACAAGCACCGACUGAGCAAAGGCCUGGGGUGCAGGAGUGCUACCAUGGUAAUGGACAGAGUUAUCGAGGCACAUACUCCACCACUGUCACAGGAAGAACCUGCCAAGCUUGGUCAUCUAUGACACCACACUCGCAUAGUCGGACCCCAGAAUACUACCCAAAUGCUGGCUUGAUCAUGAACUACUGCAGGAAUCCAGAUGCUGUGGCAGCUCCUUAUUGUUAUACGAGGGAUCCCGGUGUCAGGUGGGAGUACUGCAACCUGACGCAAUGCUCAGACGCAGAAGGGACUGCCGUCGCGCCUCCGACUGUUACCCCGGUUCCAAGCCUAGAGGCUCCUUCCGAACAAGCACCGACUGAGCAGAGGCCUGGGGUGCAGGAGUGCUACCACGGUAAUGGACAGAGUUAUCGAGGCACAUACUCCACCACUGUCACUGGAAGAACCUGCCAAGCUUGGUCAUCUAUGACACCACACUCGCAUAGUCGGACCCCAGAAUACUACCCAAAUGCUGGCUUGAUCAUGAACUACUGCAGGAAUCCAGAUGCUGUGGCAGCUCCUUAUUGUUAUACGAGGGAUCCCGGUGUCAGGUGGGAGUACUGCAACCUGACGCAAUGCUCAGACGCAGAAGGGACUGCCGUCGCGCCUCCGACUGUUACCCCGGUUCCAAGCCUAGAGGCUCCUUCCGAACAAGCACCGACUGAGCAAAGGCCUGGGGUGCAGGAGUGCUACCAUGGUAAUGGACAGAGUUAUCGAGGCACAUACUCCACCACUGUCACAGGAAGAACCUGCCAAGCUUGGUCAUCUAUGACACCACACUCGCAUAGUCGGACCCCAGAAUACUACCCAAAUGCUGGCUUGAUCAUGAACUACUGCAGGAAUCCAGAUGCUGUGGCAGCUCCUUAUUGUUAUACGAGGGAUCCCGGUGUCAGGUGGGAGUACUGCAACCUGACGCAAUGCUCAGACGCAGAAGGGACUGCCGUCGCGCCUCCGACUGUUACCCCGGUUCCAAGCCUAGAGGCUCCUUCCGAACAAGCACCGACUGAGCAAAGGCCUGGGGUGCAGGAGUGCUACCAUGGUAAUGGACAGAGUUAUCGAGGCACAUACUCCACCACUGUCACAGGAAGAACCUGCCAAGCUUGGUCAUCUAUGACACCACACUCGCAUAGUCGGACCCCAGAAUACUACCCAAAUGCUGGCUUGAUCAUGAACUACUGCAGGAAUCCAGAUGCUGUGGCAGCUCCUUAUUGUUAUACGAGGGAUCCCGGUGUCAGGUGGGAGUACUGCAACCUGACGCAAUGCUCAGACGCAGAAGGGACUGCCGUCGCGCCUCCGACUGUUACCCCGGUUCCAAGCCUAGAGGCUCCUUCCGAACAAGCACCGACUGAGCAAAGGCCUGGGGUGCAGGAGUGCUACCAUGGUAAUGGACAGAGUUAUCGAGGCACAUACUCCACCACUGUCACAGGAAGAACCUGCCAAGCUUGGUCAUCUAUGACACCACACUCGCAUAGUCGGACCCCAGAAUACUACCCAAAUGCUGGCUUGAUCAUGAACUACUGCAGGAAUCCAGAUGCUGUGGCAGCUCCUUAUUGUUAUACGAGGGAUCCCGGUGUCAGGUGGGAGUACUGCAACCUGACGCAAUGCUCAGACGCAGAAGGGACUGCCGUCGCGCCUCCGACUGUUACCCCGGUUCCAAGCCUAGAGGCUCCUUCCGAACAAGCACCGACUGAGCAGAGGCCUGGGGUGCAGGAGUGCUACCACGGUAAUGGACAGAGUUAUCGAGGCACAUACUCCACCACUGUCACUGGAAGAACCUGCCAAGCUUGGUCAUCUAUGACACCACACUCGCAUAGUCGGACCCCAGAAUACUACCCAAAUGCUGGCUUGAUCAUGAACUACUGCAGGAAUCCAGAUCCUGUGGCAGCCCCUUAUUGUUAUACGAGGGAUCCCAGUGUCAGGUGGGAGUACUGCAACCUGACACAAUGCUCAGACGCAGAAGGGACUGCCGUCGCGCCUCCAACUAUUACCCCGAUUCCAAGCCUAGAGGCUCCUUCUGAACAAGCACCAACUGAGCAAAGGCCUGGGGUGCAGGAGUGCUACCACGGAAAUGGACAGAGUUAUCAAGGCACAUACUUCAUUACUGUCACAGGAAGAACCUGCCAAGCUUGGUCAUCUAUGACACCACACUCGCAUAGUCGGACCCCAGCAUACUACCCAAAUGCUGGCUUGAUCAAGAACUACUGCCGAAAUCCAGAUCCUGUGGCAGCCCCUUGGUGUUAUACAACAGAUCCCAGUGUCAGGUGGGAGUACUGCAACCUGACACGAUGCUCAGAUGCAGAAUGGACUGCCUUCGUCCCUCCGAAUGUUAUUCUGGCUCCAAGCCUAGAGGCUUUUUUUGAACAAGCACUGACUGAGGAAACCCCCGGGGUACAGGACUGCUACUACCAUUAUGGACAGAGUUACCGAGGCACAUACUCCACCACUGUCACAGGAAGAACUUGCCAAGCUUGGUCAUCUAUGACACCACACCAGCAUAGUCGGACCCCAGAAAACUACCCAAAUGCUGGCCUGACCAGGAACUACUGCAGGAAUCCAGAUGCUGAGAUUCGCCCUUGGUGUUACACCAUGGAUCCCAGUGUCAGGUGGGAGUACUGCAACCUGACACAAUGCCUGGUGACAGAAUCAAGUGUCCUUGCAACUCUCACGGUGGUCCCAGAUCCAAGCACAGAGGCUUCUUCUGAAGAAGCACCAACGGAGCAAAGCCCCGGGGUCCAGGAUUGCUACCAUGGUGAUGGACAGAGUUAUCGAGGCUCAUUCUCUACCACUGUCACAGGAAGGACAUGUCAGUCUUGGUCCUCUAUGACACCACACUGGCAUCAGAGGACAACAGAAUAUUAUCCAAAUGGUGGCCUGACCAGGAACUACUGCAGGAAUCCAGAUGCUGAGAUUAGUCCUUGGUGUUAUACCAUGGAUCCCAAUGUCAGAUGGGAGUACUGCAACCUGACACAAUGUCCAGUGACAGAAUCAAGUGUCCUUGCGACGUCCACGGCUGUUUCUGAACAAGCACCAACGGAGCAAAGCCCCACAGUCCAGGACUGCUACCAUGGUGAUGGACAGAGUUAUCGAGGCUCAUUCUCCACCACUGUUACAGGAAGGACAUGUCAGUCUUGGUCCUCUAUGACACCACACUGGCAUCAGAGAACCACAGAAUACUACCCAAAUGGUGGCCUGACCAGGAACUACUGCAGGAAUCCAGAUGCUGAGAUUCGCCCUUGGUGUUAUACCAUGGAUCCCAGUGUCAGAUGGGAGUACUGCAACCUGACGCAAUGUCCAGUGAUGGAAUCAACUCUCCUCACAACUCCCACGGUGGUCCCAGUUCCAAGCACAGAGCUUCCUUCUGAAGAAGCACCAACUGAAAACAGCACUGGGGUCCAGGACUGCUACCGAGGUGAUGGACAGAGUUAUCGAGGCACACUCUCCACCACUAUCACAGGAAGAACAUGUCAGUCUUGGUCGUCUAUGACACCACAUUGGCAUCGGAGGAUCCCAUUAUACUAUCCAAAUGCUGGCCUGACCAGGAACUACUGCAGGAAUCCAGAUGCUGAGAUUCGCCCUUGGUGUUACACCAUGGAUCCCAGUGUCAGGUGGGAGUACUGCAACCUGACACGAUGUCCAGUGACAGAAUCGAGUGUCCUCACAACUCCCACAGUGGCCCCGGUUCCAAGCACAGAGGCUCCUUCUGAACAAGCACCACCUGAGAAAAGCCCUGUGGUCCAGGAUUGCUACCAUGGUGAUGGACGGAGUUAUCGAGGCAUAUCCUCCACCACUGUCACAGGAAGGACCUGUCAAUCUUGGUCAUCUAUGAUACCACACUGGCAUCAGAGGACCCCAGAAAACUACCCAAAUGCUGGCCUGACCGAGAACUACUGCAGGAAUCCAGAUUCUGGGAAACAACCCUGGUGUUACACAACCGAUCCGUGUGUGAGGUGGGAGUACUGCAAUCUGACACAAUGCUCAGAAACAGAAUCAGGUGUCCUAGAGACUCCCACUGUUGUUCCAGUUCCAAGCAUGGAGGCUCAUUCUGAAGCAGCACCAACUGAGCAAACCCCUGUGGUCCGGCAGUGCUACCAUGGUAAUGGCCAGAGUUAUCGAGGCACAUUCUCCACCACUGUCACAGGAAGGACAUGUCAAUCUUGGUCAUCCAUGACACCACACCGGCAUCAGAGGACCCCAGAAAACUACCCAAAUGAUGGCCUGACAAUGAACUACUGCAGGAAUCCAGAUGCCGAUACAGGCCCUUGGUGUUUUACCAUGGACCCCAGCAUCAGGUGGGAGUACUGCAACCUGACGCGAUGCUCAGACACAGAAGGGACUGUGGUCGCUCCUCCGACUGUCAUCCAGGUUCCAAGCCUAGGGCCUCCUUCUGAACAAGACUGUAUGUUUGGGAAUGGGAAAGGAUACCGGGGCAAGAAGGCAACCACUGUUACUGGGACGCCAUGCCAGGAAUGGGCUGCCCAGGAGCCCCAUAGACACAGCACGUUCAUUCCAGGGACAAAUAAAUGGGCAGGUCUGGAAAAAAAUUACUGCCGUAACCCUGAUGGUGACAUCAAUGGUCCCUGGUGCUACACAAUGAAUCCAAGAAAACUUUUUGACUACUGUGAUAUCCCUCUCUGUGCAUCCUCUUCAUUUGAUUGUGGGAAGCCUCAAGUGGAGCCGAAGAAAUGUCCUGGAAGCAUUGUAGGGGGGUGUGUGGCCCACCCACAUUCCUGGCCCUGGCAAGUCAGUCUCAGAACAAGGUUUGGAAAGCACUUCUGUGGAGGCACCUUAAUAUCCCCAGAGUGGGUGCUGACUGCUGCUCACUGCUUGAAGAAGUCCUCAAGGCCUUCAUCCUACAAGGUCAUCCUGGGUGCACACCAAGAAGUGAACCUCGAAUCUCAUGUUCAGGAAAUAGAAGUGUCUAGGCUGUUCUUGGAGCCCACACAAGCAGAUAUUGCCUUGCUAAAGCUAAGCAGGCCUGCCGUCAUCACUGACAAAGUAAUGCCAGCUUGUCUGCCAUCCCCAGACUACAUGGUCACCGCCAGGACUGAAUGUUACAUCACUGGCUGGGGAGAAACCCAAGGUACCUUUGGGACUGGCCUUCUCAAGGAAGCCCAGCUCCUUGUUAUUGAGAAUGAAGUGUGCAAUCACUAUAAGUAUAUUUGUGCUGAGCAUUUGGCCAGAGGCACUGACAGUUGCCAGGGUGACAGUGGAGGGCCUCUGGUUUGCUUCGAGAAGGACAAAUACAUUUUACAAGGAGUCACUUCUUGGGGUCUUGGCUGUGCACGCCCCAAUAAGCCUGGUGUCUAUGCUCGUGUUUCAAGGUUUGUUACUUGGAUUGAGGGAAUGAUGAGAAAUAAUUAAUUGGACGGGAGACAGAGUGAAGCAUCAACCUACUUAGAAGCUGAAACGUGGGUAAGGAUUUAGCAUGCUGGAAAUAAUAGACAGCAAUCAAACGAAGACACUGUUCCCAGCUACCAGCUAUGCCAAACCUUGGCAUUUUUGGUAUUUUUGUGUAUAAGCUUUUAAGGUCUGACUGACAAAUUCUGUAUUAAGGUGUCAUAGCUAUGACAUUUGUUAAAAAUAAACUCUGCACUUAUUUUGAUUUGAA